GGCACAGCGGACACCAGGACUCCAAAAUGGCGUCAGUUGGUGAGUGUCCGGCCCCAGUACCAGUGAAGGACAAGAAACUUCUGGAGGUCAAACUGGGGGAGCUGCCAAGCUGGAUCUUGAUGCGGGACUUCAGUCCUAGUGGCAUUUUCGGAGCGUUUCAAAGAGGUUACUACCGGUACUACAACAAGUACAUCAAUGUGAAGAAGGGGAGCAUCUCGGGGAUUACCAUGGUGCUGGCAUGCUACGUGCUCUUUAGCUACUCCUUUUCCUACAAGCAUCUCAAGCACGAGCGGCUCCGCAAAUACCACUGAAGAGGACACACUCUGCACCCCCCCACCCCACGACCUUGGCCCGAGCCCCUCCGUGAGGAACACAAUCUCAAUCGUUGCUGAAUCCUUUCAUAUCCUAAUAGGAAUUAACCUCCAAAUAAAACAUGACUGGUA